AGCAAAUACCUUUUGUUUCUCUCACGUUGGGGCUACUUGUUUUAGGGCGCAAAGGAACGGCCUCGAAAGGGGGUCCUUCCCCAGCCGAGAACCAGGAAUCUUCCCUCGGCCCGCGCGCGCGACCGGCCGGUGCGCCGCGGCCCGCGGACAAUCCUCCAAACACAGACUGUUUGACUUAGAAUCUUCCCUUUUUUACUCCAUUCAAGAGCAGCAUUCAUAAAUUUCCAGAAUGGAGAUCUCCUCUCAUCAGUCUCACCUCCUGCAGCAACUGAACGAGCAGCGCAGGCAAGAUGUAUUUUGUGACUGCAGUAUUCUAGUUGAAGGGAAGGUCUUCAAAGCACAUCGAAAUGUAUUAUUCGCUAGUAGCGGCUACUUUAAAAUGCUUCUUUCUCAGAAUUCAAAGGAGACGAGUCAGCCAACCACAGCUACAUUUCAGGCUUUCUCCCCUGACACUUUUACAGUUAUCUUGGACUUCGUAUAUUCUGGCAAACUGUCUCUUACUGGUCAGAAUGUCAUAGAAGUGAUGUCGGCUGCUAGCUUCCUUCAGAUGACUGAUGUCAUAAGUGUAUGUAAGACUUUUAUUAAAUCUUCCUUAGACAUUAGUGAGAAAGAAAAAGAUCGCUAUUUCAGUCUCUCAGAUAAAGAUGCCAAUUCUAAUGGUGUAGAACGUUCCUCUUUUUAUAGUGGUGGCUGGCAAGAAGGAAGCAGUUCUCCACGUUCUCACCUAAGCCCAGAGCAAGGAACAGGUAUAAUAAGUGGAAAAUCUUGGAAUAAGUAUAAUUAUCAUCCAGCCUCCCAGAAGAAUACUCAACAACCCUUGGCCAAGCAUGAACCAAGGAAAGAGUCCAUUAAAAAGACCAAACAUUUGAGAUUGUCACAGCCUUCUGAAGUUACUCAUUAUAAGUCAAGCAAACGAGAAGUACGAACAUCUGAUUCUUCCAGCCAUGUUUCCCAGUCUGAAGAACAAGCACAGAUUGAUGCUGAAAUGGACUCUACUCCUGUUGGCUAUCAGUACGGUCAAGGAUCUGAUGUCACAUCCAAAAGCUUUCCAGAUGAUCUGCCUCGGAUGCGAUUCAAGUGCCCGUACUGCACACAUGUGGUGAAGCGGAAGGCAGACCUAAAGCGCCACCUUCGUUGUCAUACAGGAGAAAGGCCCUAUCCAUGUCAAGCUUGUGGAAAAAGAUUUAGCAGGCUAGACCAUCUAAGUAGCCAUUUUCGAACAAUUCACCAGGCAUGUAAACUCAUCUGCAGAAAAUGUAAACGUCAUGUGACAGAUCUAACAGGGCAAGUGGUACAGGAGGGAACCAGGCGCUACAGACUGUGUAAUGAGUGUCUUGCAGAAUUUGGCAUAGACAGCCUCCCCAUUGACUUGGAAGCUGAACAACAUCUUAUGUCCCCAUCAGAUGGAGAUAAGGAUUCCAGAUGGCACUUGAGUGAAGAUGAGAAUAGAUCCUAUGUGGAGAUUGUAGAAGAUGGGUCUGCUGAUCUGGUCAUCCAACAGGUUGAUGAUAGUGAAGAAGAAGAAGAAAAAGAAAUUAAGCCCAACAUUAGGUAGCUGUAAUGUGAACCAACAGAGCUGGCAUGUCUGCAAUUUACAUUGACUUCCUGUAUCUCUCUCUUUCUAUGGUCGGAGUCUAGUUAACAAAUUUAUCACACUGACUUUAAAGAAAUGAUCUGAUAUAACUUGCAUGCUUUCUGAACAGGCCAUUGUAUCCAUUCUGAACUUUGUUGCCCUAAAAUGUGUUGCUGCACUGGAAAGAAAGAACUAGCUUGAGUUGGCUUGAUGGAUGAACAAUUAUCCUCUUACUUUCAUUACAAUCCUCUUACUUUAUUCCAGAGAUACCUUUUUCUUUUAAUAUUGGAGGAUCUACUUAGCAAACUUUUUUCAAAGAAAAUACUUUAAAUAAAUUCACCACAACCAAACUUUAUGUAAGACAAUUUCAAGGUGUUUCAAAAACACAUAACUACCAAUGUUUAAUUUCACAGGGAACCAGUUAAGAGCACAUUUAAGGAUCUGGCAACCCACCUUACUAAACAAAUUAGUCUUUCUAUUAAUUUGAGAUCUGAAACAACCUGUCAUUACUCUGAUAUCCUGAACGUUUAAGGAUUAUGGAAGAAGACUAAAGUGUUUGAAAUCAUUCAUAUUUGAAAUUUUUAUCAUUAGCUUAAAAAUUACUCUCAGUAUUGUUAAAAAAAAAAAAAAGUAGAGGCUGGCCAAAGAUUAUAUACAGAUAUUUUCUUAAAGCAGGAAACUAAUGUUGCCUAAAAGUCAAGGUAGUUUGUGAAGACAAUCUGUCAAUAUGGUUGUCCAUCUCUCUAAAGAAAAGCAGGCUGGGCGCUGUGGCUCAUGCCUAUAAUCCCAAUACUUUGGGAGGCCGAGGCAGGCGGAUCACAAGGUCAGGAGUUUGAAACCAGCCUGGCCAACAUGGUGAAACCUCGUCUCUACUAAAAAAUACAAAAUUAGCCGGGCAUGGUGGCGGGUGCCUAUAAUCCCAGCUACUCGGGAGGCUGAGGCAGGAGAAUCGAUUGAACCUGGAAGGCAGAAGUUGCAGUGAGCCGAGAUCACACCAUUGCACUCCAGCCUGGGCAACAAGAGCGAAACUCCGUCUCAAAAAAAAAAGGAAAACAAACUAGGAGGUUCUUACCAUAUGUGAGUGAUUUCUAACGUUUAUGUAGUGCUAUAUUAUUUAUAAAGUACUCUCUCAUGUAUUUUCUCAGUGAGGUGGAUACUAUCUCCGAUUUACAAAUGAGGAAAUUAAGGUCAGAAAGUCUGAGAGAGAAAACUGAUGAUUGGACAGGAUCUGAUUUUAAACAAUCCUCUUUCAGCCUUCUCUCCCUGUAUGUCUCCUGAAAUGGCAAAGAAUAGAAGUCAAACCUCACCAGUUGGCAGUCAUUAUAAAAAUAAGCCAAUCAGAAUUAGAAAGUAUGAAAGGAGGAAUUGAAUCAUUUUCAACAACAUACAAUAUCUUGAUCUAGAGAUUUUCAAAUAAUGCUAAGUAAUGUCCCUACAGUACCUAUUGGUAUGUUUUUAUGUCACGUUAUUUAUAUGUAAAUUUAAAGUAUAAAACUAUUUGAACAAAUUAUUCACUUAAAUAUGUUGAACAUUUUUGCUUCUCUUGUUUAUAUAAUAUUUUCAAAACAAACUUUUCUCCUAGUAUACAAAGUUUAAACUUCUCCCCUUUGGGCUGGGCCCAGUGGCUCACGCCUGUAAUCCCAGCACUUUGGGAGGCUGAGGCAGGUGGAUCACCGAGGUCGGGAGUUUGAGACCAGCCUGACCAACAUGGAGAAACCCCGUCUCUACUAAAAAUACAAAAUUAGCCGGGCGUGGUGGUGCAUGCCUGUAAUCCCAGCUACUCAGAAGGCUGAGGCAGGAGGAUAGCUUGAACCCAGGAGGCAGAGGCUGCGGUGGGCUGAGGUUGCGCCAUUGCACUCCAGCCUGGGCAACAAGAGCGAAACUCCGUCUCAAAAAAAAAAAAAAAAAAAACUUCUCCCCUGCAUAAAUUAUGAAACAUUCCAAAAUUACAGCUAAAUUAGAGAAGCAUUGUUUCAGUUCUAAAGGUAAAAUCUAAAUAUCCGAAGUAAAGAACUGAGCUUCAUAAAGGUCUCUUCUGCAAGUUAUCACAGUGAAGCUUGAUAGAAUUUCACUGUAUAUGGAGAGGCUCCAUCUAUUUUACUGUUUUCUUUUUUGUUUUUGUUUUUUUUUCGAGACGGAGUCUCGCUCUGUCGCCCAGGCUGGAGUGCAGUGGUGCAAUCUCAGCUCACUGCAAGCUCCACCUCCCGGGUUCUCGCCAUUCUCCUGCCUCAGCCUCCCGAGUAGCUGGGACUUACAGGCGCCCACCACCACUCCCAGCUAAUUUUUUGUAUUUUUAAUAGAGAUGGGGUUUCACCGUGUUAGCCAGGAUGGUCUCAAUCUCCUGAUCUCGUGAUCCGCCCCCCUCGGCCUCCCAAAGUGCUGGGAUUACAGGCGUGAGCCACUGCGCCCAGCCAAUUUUACUGUAUUUUUAAAUGCCAUGACAUACCUCAAAAUUAUCCUUUUUAUGUUACUAUUUUCUCUUGUUCUUUCAUUAAUUAUUGUCCUUGAUACCAAUUUCUAGGCUAAAUUGGUUACUUUCUUUUAAAAAAUUUAAAAAUAGAUGAAUAACCACUUGUUUCAUGGUACUUAAUUGAGACUUUUUCAAGAUUCCCCUGAUGGCACAUUUGCAGUUGCUUCAAGACUGGAUGAUGUGCAUUGAGUUCUCUGUUCUCCCAACAUGGCUGUUCCUAAAUCAGGAUUCUGGUUUUUUUGAGAUGGACUCUCGCUCUGUUGUCCAAGCUGGAGUGCAGUGGCGUGAUCUCGCUCACCACAACCUCUGCCUCCCGGGUUCAAGCGAUUCUCCUGCCUCAGCCUCCUGAGUAGCCGGGACUACAGGCAUGUGCCACCAUGCCUGGCUAAUUUUUGUAUUUUUAGUAGAGACAGGGUUUCGCUAUGUUGGCCAGGCUGGUCUCGAACUCCUGACCUCGUGAUCUGCCCGCCUCAGCCUCCCAAAGUGCUGGGAUUACAGGCGUGAGCCAGCACGCCCGGCCUAAAUCAGGAUUCUUAACAAUUAAAGUGUAUCUGAAUGAGGAAGGAAACGCUUGUCAUUCUCUAGUCUUACCCAAUUAAUACUGACACCUUUUGAAAUUAAAACCUGAUUUUUUAGUUGUUGGAGCCAGUAGGAAAAAUGGCUGAUUUGAACUUUUUUCCUAUAAAUGAAGUAGUGCUUGCAUGUGUGUACUCUAAUGCACUUUAGUCUAUGAUCUAAAUGUCCUUUUAUGCUAUUAUCUUCUGCAUGCAAACUUUACAUACAUCAGCAUGAAUAUCCAACAUUCACUGAACACAGUGCCACCAGCACUUGUAAUUGCCUUUUCAGAAAUAAUGCUUUCUCAUAAUUGUUUAUAACGAGCAUCAAACUAUCCCCACAAAAUGAUCAAGUUCACCAAACUAGACAAAGAAUCUGUUGUAUCAUUUUAACAUCAUAGAAGAACAUUUAAGACAUGUUUGUAAGUUGUAAAUAAUGACUCCAGUUAUAGCAUAUAUAUCUAAGACGUUAGAGACCAGUUAUUUUCUAGAGUGAAACUGUCUAUUGAUGAUUGAGAAAAUUGAAUUCUUUGGUUUUUACAUGUGGGCAAAUGUUACAUAGGGGUAUAAUCUGUUUAAAUAAGCUUUAUUUAUGCCAAGGAUUUUUUUUUUAAUAUCAAGACUUGGUUAGACCAAAGUUUGCUCUUGCAGGAAUGCCAUUUAUCAGCUUCUGAAUGCCCUUCUAACUCCAUUACCCUCAAGAGUGUCUGGGUAUAGGAUGAAGCAUUACAAAAAGAAAGCACCACUGCAGUCAUGCCUAGUGUCUGGGAGAAACAAAAUGGACUAGACCUGCAGUUUAAAAUAAUUUAACCCGAGAAACUCUUCAAAUGAAUUGUUUCCUAAAGAUGCUCAAAUUUAAGGGAUAAACUCUAAAAUCAGAGCUGCUGUGGUUAAAGUCCCCCACAAACCUUUCCCCAGACACCUCUGCAGAACUCAGGUGCACAAUGUUGAAAACCAUGGAAUUAGACAACUUCCUGAAUUCCCUUUGAGCCUUGCAGCCUCAUUUCGUUACUCCUGUUACUCACGGUGCUUAUAAGCAGGUAACCAUAUGGUCUCUUAGUGAAGCAAAUCACAUCCUUAGCACAUGAUGUUCCUUCUAUGGGUAUCAGAUCUUAAGACUUUUUAAAAUUUAGGAACAAAUGUUUCAAUAUUAUAUUUUCAGUAAUGCAAUCAAAAUAAGCAUAGUUACUGUUUUCUGUACGGCUAAGUACUGCCUAAUGGAUGAAAGAAGUUUGGUGCUUCAAUUAUUUAUGAGCUCAGAACUCAAUUCAUUAAAGUUAUUUUGCCAAGUCAUGCCAAGAUAUAUUGAAAUUUCCACUCAUAUUGGUUUUUAAAAUUUUUUUUAGUCCUAAAAUUAAUAAGUAUGGAAAAUCACUAAAAGCAGUGUAGGAUAAGGUGUGUUUAACUGGCCGGGCACGGUGGCUCAUGCCUGUAAUCCUAGCACUUUGGGAGGCCGAGGCGGGCGGAUCACUUAAGGCCAGGUGUUCGAGACCAUCCUGGCCAACAUGGUGAAACCCCGUCUCUAGUAAAAAUACAAAAAAUAGCUGGGCAUGAUGGUGGGUGCCUGUAAUCCCAGGUACUCGGGAGGCUGAGGCAGGAGAAUCGCUUGAACCCGGGAGGUGGAGGUUGCAGUGGCCGAGAUCGCACCACUGCACUCCAGCCUGGGUGACAGAGCGAGACUCCAUCAAAAAAAAAAAAAAAAAAAAAAAAGAUGUGUUUAACUGGGAAGGGUGAUAAUAAUAGAAUAAUAGGUACAGGAGGACCAAACUUUAGAUUAUAAACCAGAAAGUUUUGUUAUUUUAUAUAAGUGUAUCAGUAUUACUAUUUAUCAUUUAUAUAGCAUUUUAUAUUUGCAAAGUGUUUAAUAAUUUUUGUUAUUCUUUACAUAUAUAUGAAAUAGGACAGUUAUCCCACAUGAACGGUAAAUAAAUUGAGGCACAGAACAGUAAAAAAACCUCAGGGUCAGGCGUGGUGGCUCACACCUGUAAUCCCAGCACUUUGGGAGGCCAAGGCGGGUGGAUCACUUUAGGUCAAGAGUUGGAGACCAGCCUGGGGCAAUAUAGUGAAACCCCUUCUCUACUAAAAAUACAAAAAUUAGCCAGGCAUGGUGGUGGGCACCUGUAAUCCCAGCUACUCUGGGGGCUGAGACAGGAGAAUUGCUUGAACUCAGGAGGCGGAGGUUGCAGUGAGCCAAGAUCACGCUACUGCACUCCAGGCUGGGUGACAGAGCGAGACUCCACCUCAAAAAAAAAAAAAAAAAAAAAAAAAAGAACCUAAGACAACCCAGUGAAAUGGUAGCAAAAAAUAGGAAAUAUAAUGAUCACAUUUUCUGAAUCCUAGACCAUCAGCCUAAUUCACUGAGGUGUGUUGUGUAUCACUCUAUUUUAUAGAUGAUUUUAUAUAAGUAACAGUGGAUUGUUUUAAAGCUGACGUCAUUGUAUGUGGAUACAUUCUAUAUGGAAUAAAUGUUAUGUAAAGGA